AGAUUCUCGCAAAUCUGGAAGCGGAUCGCGUGGAGUGACGGUCACACCGCGGCGAAUUAAUUUCCAAAGACUCAUGUUACAUGAGAAAGCCACCAAGAAGACCAAAGAAAAGGAGACAAGGAUGGCUCUUCCUCAGGGAUGCUUGACUUUCAGGGAUGUGGCUAUAGAAUUCUCUUUGGAGGAGUGGAAAUGCCUGAACCCUGCACAGAGGGCUUUAUACAGGGCCGUGAUGUUGGAGAACUACAGGAACCUGGAGUCUGUGGAUAGCUCUUUAAAAUCCAUGACGGAGUUCUCAUCAACAGGGCACGGUAAUACAGGAGAAGUGAUCCACACAGGGACAUUGCAAAGACAUAAAAGUCAUCACAUUGGAGAUUUUUGCUUCCCAGAAAUCAAGAAAGAUAUUCAUGACUUUGAGUUUCAGUGGCAAGAAAUUAAAAGAAAUGGCCAUGAAGCACCCAUGACAAAAAUCAAAAAGUUGACUGGUAGUACAGACCGACGUGAUCAAAGGCAUGCUGGAAACAAGCCUAUUAAAGAUCAGCUUGGAUCAAGCUUUUAUUCACAUCUGCCUGAACUGCACGAAUUUCAGACUGAAGGGAAAAUUGAUAAUCAAGUGGAGAAGUCUAUCAACAAUGCUUCCUUGGUUUCAACAUCCCAAAGAAUUUCUUGUAGGCUCAAAACCCAUAUUUCUAAUAGGUAUGGGAAGAACUUUCUCCAUUCUUCAUUAUUGACACAAAUCCAGGAAGAACACAUGAGAGAAAAACCUUUCCAAUGUAAUGAGUGUGGCAAAGCCUUUAAUUAUAGCUCACAUUUAAGAAGACAUCAUGUAACCCAUUCAGGAGAGAAACAAUAUAAAUGUGAUGUAUGUGGCAAAGUGUUUCAUCAAAAGCAAUACCUUGCAUGGCACCAUAGAGUUCAUACUGGAGAAAAACCUUACAAGUGUAAUGAGUGUUCCAAGACCUUCGGUCACAAGUCAUCUCUUACACGCCAUCAUAGACUUCAUACUGGAGAAAAACCUUACAAGUGUAAUGAGUGUGGUAAGACCUUCAGUCAGACGUCAUCCCUUGUAGGGCAUCGUAGACGUCAUACUGGAGAGAAACCUUACAAAUGUGAAGGAUGUGACAAAGUUUACAGUUGCAGAUCACAACUUGAAACACAUAGGCGAAUUCAUACUGGAGAGAAACCAUACAAAUGUAAGGUUUGUGACAAAGCUUUUAGGCAUAAUUCAUGCCUUUCACGCCAUAACAGAGUUCAUACUGAAGAGAAACCUUACACAUGUAAUGAAUGUGGCAAGGUUUUCCAGCGUGAUUCAUACCUUGCACAACAUCAGAGAGUUCAUACUGGAGAGAAACCUUACACAUGUAAUGAAUGUGGUAAGGUUUUUAAUCAAAAAGCACACCUUGCAUGUCAUUAUAGGCUUCAUACUGGAGAGAAACCUUACAAGUGUAAUGAGUGUGGCAAGACCUUCAGUCAGAAGUCAUCCCUUGUGGGCCAUCGUAGACUUCAUACCGGAGAAAAACCUUACAACUGUCAUGAGUGUGGCAAGACCUUUGCUCGAAAUUCAUCCCUUCUAAUUCAUAAGGCAAUUCAUACUGGAGAGAAACCUUACAAGUGUAAUGAAUGUGGCAAGGUUUUUAAUCAACAGUCAAACCUUGCACAACAUCAGAGAGUUCAUACUGGAGAGAAACCUUACAGGUGUAAUGAGUGUGGCAAGACCUUCAGUCAUAUGUCAUCCUUUGUAUACCAUUAUAGACUUCAUAGUGGAGAGAAACCUUACAAGUGCAAUGAGUGUGGCAAGACCUUCAGUCAUAUGUCAUCCUUUGUAUGCCAUCAUAGACUUCAUACUGGAGAAAAUCCUUAUAAGUGCAAUGAGUGUGGCAAAGCCUUUAGUGGGCAGUCAUCACUUAUUCAUCAUCAAGCAAUCCAUGGUAUAGGGAAACUUUACAAAUGUAAUGAUUCUCACAAAGUCCUCAGUAAUGCUACAAGCAUUGCAAAUCAUUAGAGAAUCCAUAAUGAAGAGAGAUCUUACAAGUGUAGUAAAUGUGGCAGAUAUUUCAGACAUUGUUCAUAGCUUGCAGUUCAUCAGUGAACUCAUACUGGAAAGAAACGUUACAAAUGUCAUGAUUGCAGCAAGGUCUUCAGUCAAGCUUCAUCUUAUGCAAAACACAGGAGAAUUCAUAUGGGAGAGAACCUCACAACUGUGAUAAUUGUGGCAGUCAUUUUUUUUUCUUUUUUCAGAUGAAGUCUUACUCUUUUGUCCAGGCUGGGGUGCAGUGGCGUGAUCUCGGCUCACGGCAACCUCCACCUCCCAGGUUCAUACGAUUCUCCUUCCUAGCCUCCUGAGUAGCUGGGACUACAAGCAUGCUCCACCAAGCCUGGCUAAUUUUUAUGUUUUUAGUAGAGACAGGGUUUCACCAUGUUGGCCUGGUUGCUCUCAACUCUUGAUCUUGUGAUCCGCCUGCCUCGGCCUCCCAAAGUGCUGGUAUUACAGGCAUGAGCCACCACGCCCAGUGUGGCAAUGUCUUUACUUUACAUUCACACCGCAUUAGACAUCAGGGAAUCUAUACUGGACAGAAAUCUUACAAAUGGAAUAGGUGUGGCAAUGUCUUUAGUCUGAGGUCACUCCUUGCAGAACAGUAGAAAAUUCAUUUUUGAGAUAAUUGUCCCAAAUACAAUGACUAUAGAAAAUGACAAACUUUAAUUGACAUUAGAGUCAAUUCUGCAUUGACUAGAGUUUGAGUUGACUUAACAUUGAGUUCAAGCAUUAAUUGACAUAAAAAGUGUUUACGUCAAGAAGAAUGGGCAGGGUGCAGUUGCUCACACCUAUAAUCCCAGCACUUUGGGAGGCCAAGGCAGGCAGAUCACUUGAGGUCAGCAGUUUGAGACCAGCUGGGCCAACAGACCUGAACCAGUUUGCCCAGCCUGUUUUUUCUUUCCUUCUUUCUUUCUUUUCUUUUCUUUCUUUCUUUUUUUUUUUUUUUUUUUUGAGACAGAGUCUUUCUCUUGUCGCCCAAGCUGGCGUGCAAUGGCACAAUCUUGGUUCACUGCAACCUCCACCUCCUGCAUUCAAGCAAUUCUCUUUUCUAAGCCUCCCAAGUAGCUGGGAUUUCAGAUGUGUGCCACCACACCACAUAGUCCCUCUCCACAGAGAUGGUUGAGAAGGCUGAUGGAAAAGCCAGAUACUUGUUCUACAGCUUUCCCUGACACUAGUAUAUCAUCCACAUACUGGAGCAUAGAUAUACACUUUGGGAUGCUCAUCUUUUCUAACACCUCCUCAAGAAUUUGGCCAAACAAGUUAGGAGAAUCUGUAAAUCCUUGGGGUAAGACUGUCCAGCAGUAUUGUUGUUUUCACCCAGAGUGAGAAUCUUCCCAUUCAAAAGUGAAUAUAUCCUGACUAUCUUCAGCUAAAGGACAUGCCCAGAAGGCAUCUUUCAGGUCUAUUUCUGUAAACCACUGAUGGUCAUAUGGAAUUUUGCUGAGAAUAGUAUAUGGAUUGGGAACAACAGGAUGAGUGGUUUGAACAGUUUGAUUAAUGGCUUGAAGAUCUUCUACAAGUCAGUAUCACCAAUCUGACUACUUUACAAGUAAUAUUGGAGUAGUAUAGGGAGACAUGCACAGUUCAAGUAGCCCAUCUCAGAUAAGGCUCUCAAUUAGAGGUUUUAAACCUAAUCUACCUUCUAAGGGAAUUGGAUAUUGGUUUCUUUUCACUGUUUCCCUGGGAGUUUUUAACUUUAUGUGAAUUGGAGGAACUUGUAGCUUCCUUCAAUUUCCCUCCCUUGACCACUCAUUAGCAUUGAUGUAGCUUUCUUCUGCUGUAGUAAACAGGUUUAAUGAAGUGAAGAAUCCUUCUGGGCUUACACGCAAGCCUAUACCUAACUUUGCCAUUAGGCCACUUCCUAACAAGUUUGUCCCAGCCUUAGGAAGUAGCAAAAAUUUAACAUUGGUUGAUCGGGUUUCAAAUCUGACUUCUGUUUUUUCUGAGACUUUGGCUUUAAAUCCUUCCCCUUUGACUCCUAAAACUUGAAGUUCUUCUAAUAAACAAUUUAUAUUAGAGGGCACAAAACAAACAGAGGAGUGGGAAGCUCCUGAGUCUAUUAGAAAAGUAAUAAGUUCGGCUGGGUGCCAUGGCUCACACCUGUAGUCCCAGCACUUUGGGAGGCCAAGGUGGGCGGAUCACCUGAGGUCGAGAGUUCGAGACCAGCCUGACCCACAUGGAGAAACCC